UUCCUGAAUGCUCCUCCAGAGUUGGUGUCGACAGAGGCCUCCUUAUGGCUCCCUGCAGCAGGUCGUGCCGCACCUCCGCCUCCGCCUCCGUCCCCCGAGUCUCCAUGUGUUCGCGGCAGGGACCGCCGGCUCCUGUAAUGAGCAGUCCCACUGUCUUUAACGGACACCUAAAGAGUGCAGAGCAAGGAGAUGGAGCGCUGGACGCCUUCAAAUACCGGGACAACCAGGAUCCAGAGCAGCGAGGGACCCACAGUGCUCCCUCAGAGGCCUCUGGACCCCACGCCCACACGUCCCUGUGACCACCCACACCCUCCCCCGACUGGCUUCUCCAUGCUGCUGUCUCCGGGACAUGAGUCGCCUGUCUGUCCCCCACGUGUGGCCAGGAGGGCAUGAGCCACCUGUCUGUCCCCUACGUGUGCCCAGGAGGGCACGAGCCGCCUGUCUGUCUGCCAUGUGUGCCCAGGAGAUACGGUGCUUUUCCUGCCAUGUCCUCAGAGCUGUGCAUGUGGCACACAGGAAGCAGUUGUCACAAAUAAACAGGAAUUUGGCCUGUGUAUGUUAGUCCUGAGAACUUGGUUAGCACGAGUCUGUUUCUGCAAGAUAACCCGUUCCUGGUGAGCAGACAGAGCUAGUCAUAGAGCCUGCUGGCAUGGGCUGUGCCAGGGCCCUGUGGGGUUGGCAGGGAAGCACGUCCUGUGUGGCCAGGUGUCCCCCGGGGAGAGAGCUCUGGGCUGUGAAUCCUUCUGGGAGGCAGGCGAAGGGCCCUGGCCUUCUGUACCCCAGUGUUUCCUGUGUGCCAACAGGAACAGGUGCUUAGCAUCUCGUGCCAUGGGGCCUCUCAGCGCCCUCCUGAGCCAGAGCUUGCUGUUGAGCUGUACAGCGCCUCGAGAGAGGCUGCCUGGGGGAGGCUGGCCUGGGACUCCUGGCAUGGGCCCACUCCGCUCAGGCACCUCUGCACCCUCCUCGAUUGUCCGUAAGGGCAGGGGGUCCCUCCGGGCCCUGGCCUAUGCCACACCCUCCGGAGGUGAAGCCGGGGUGCUCUGCUUGUUCUCGCAGUACGGCUUCUCUCACAGGGCAAAGGUCACUCGUGACGUGUCCCAGUCAAAAACGGGGUAAAGUGUGGGGAAACGCACAAAGUGUGUUUUGCUUUUUAGAGAAGAGCGGUUGAGCACACGCCAUGCUGGCUGCUCAGGUUGGGGUGCAGCCUGCAGAGAGCUUCCCGAACUUGGGGGUCCUGAGUCCGUAACUGCUCGAAGCGGUGCCUGGAUCGUCCGGGUCCCUUCUGUUUACUCACAUUGGUUGUGGAGCGCUGACUGGCUUGUGCGCUCCAGGCCUUAGAUGGGGACACAGGUGAGGAGCUAGACCCUCUCGGGGUCCUUUGAAGUGCCAGGCGCCCAGAGCACAGCAGGUGCAGGGCUUAACUCAGAACCUCCUGGAGCCCUGCCUGGCACCGUGUCAUUGGGAGUCCAUGGCACAGGCAGGUACGGGUUUCUGGUGUGCAUGGCAGAGGCGUUCUGGCGGCCUCAGCACGUGCACUUUGCCUAAGCUCACGUCCGACACACCGAGGGUUCCAGGUUCCACUCGGUAUUUCCUGAAAACAACUGCCCAGGGCACUGGCGCUGACCGGGGCCCCUGCAGACGGCUGGGUCUCCACCCCACUCCACCAGCAACCAGGCCUCCACCCCACUCCACCAGCAACCAGGCCUCCACCCCACUCCACCAGCAACCAGGCCUCCACCCCACUCCACCAGCAACCAGGCCUCCACCCCACUCCACCAGCAACCAGGCCUCCACCCCACUCCACCAGCAACCAGGCCUCCACCCCACUCCACCAGCAACCAGGCCUCCACCCCACUCCACCAGCAACCAGGCCUCCACCCCACUCCUCCAUCAACCAGGCCUCCACCCCACUCCACCAGCAACCAGGCCUCCACCCCACUCCACCAGCAACCAGGCCUCCACCCCACUCCUCCAGCAACCAGGCCUCCACCCCACUCCACCAGCAACCAGGCCUCCACCCCACUCCACCAGCAACCAGGCCUCCAUCCCACUCCUCCAGCAACCAGGCCUCCACCAGCAACCAGGCCUCCACCCCACUCCACCAGCAACCAGGCCUCCACCCCACUCCUCCAGCAACCAGGCCUCCACCCCACUCCACCAGCAGCCAGACCCAUGCUCAGGGCCUCAUCAGCGACCUUUCACCUGUGGAGCAUGGUUUACCCCAGGCCCCUUCGGCCGCUGCAGGUGUACAUCGGUGAGCUCCCGCAGGACUUCCUCCGCAUCACGCCCACACAGCAGCAGCGGCAGGUCCAGCUGGACGCCCAGGCGGCCCAGCAGCUGCAGUACGGAGGCGCAGUGGGCACCGUGGGCCGACUGAACAUCACGGUGGUACAGGCAAAGUUGGCCAAGAAUUACGGCAUGACCCGCAUGGACCCCUACUGCCGACUGCGCCUGGGCUACGCGGUGUACGAGACGCCCACGGCACACAAUGGCGCCAAGAAUCCCCGCUGGAAUAAGGUCAUCCACUGCACGGUGCCCCCAGGCGUGGACUCUUUCUAUCUCGAGAUCUUCGAUGAGAGAGCCUUCUCCAUGGACGACCGCAUUGCCUGGACCCACAUCACCAUCCCGGAGUCCCUGAGGCAGGGCAAGGUGGAGGACAAGUGGUACAGCCUGAGCGGGAGGCAGGGGGACGACAAGGAGGGCAUGAUCAACCUCGUCAUGUCCUACGCGCUGCUUCCAGCUGCCAUGGUGAUGCCACCCCAGCCCGUGGUCCUGAUGCCAACAGUGUACCAGCAGGGCGUUGGCUAUGUGCCCAUCACAGGGAUGCCCGCUGUCUGUAGCCCCGGCAUGGUGCCCGUGGCCCUGCCCCCGGCCGCCGUGAACGCCCAGCCCCGCUGUAGCGAGGAGGACCUGAAAGCCAUCCAGGACAUGUUCCCCAACAUGGACCAGGAGGUGAUCCGCUCCGUGCUGGAAGCCCAGCGAGGGAACAAGGAUGCCGCCAUCAACUCCCUGCUGCAGAUGGGGGAGGAGCCAUAGAGCCUCUGCCUCGAUGCCGUUUUGCCCCCGCUCUUUGGACACGCCGACCCGGCGCUCCCCAAGGAAUGCUGUCCCAACAAGAUUCCCGUGAAAGAGCACCCGUGUCGCCCCCUCCCGUGGACUUCUGUGCCGCCCCGUCCACACCUGUUCUUGGGUGCAUGUGGGUUUUCGGUUCCUGGCGGUCCAGGACGGGGCGGGGGCUCCCCUCCCAUCUCGUGCUGGGAGGUCUCAGCGCGCUCUCCUGUCCCUGGGACGUGCGUCUCUCCUUCUCAUGCCGUUCUGGAAAAUGCUCUUGCUGUAGAGAGCAGCUGCUUCUGCCAGGGUGUUGGAGGUGGUGGAGCGCCUUCCGAUUCCAUUCAUGGCAUUUUGUGAUGUGAUGUAAUUGGAAUAGAGCUGUUGAUUUAAGGCACACACAAUCCCUCACACUGUGGGUUUUUUUUAGAACUUCCCAGACGAAAACUCACGCCCUUGCCCUAACGCGCUUUGCUGUGAGCCUGGCCCCUGCCCAGGGCUUGGGUCUGGUGAGCUGAGCAGCUUCCUGUGGAUGGUGUGGGGCCGGCCUCUGGCCUGGCUCACCUGGCCACUGUCCAGCCAGCCUUGUGACAGACUCCGGCCUGAAGGCAGAAUGAACCCACACCUGGAGUGAGGAAGGGGGCCUGGCACGGUUGGCCAGGCUCUGCCUGAUUGCCAGCCAGCGGGCAUCUGAAGCCGGGUCCUUCGCCCGCCGGAGGCUGCCGUCCGUCUCUCCUGCUGCGCUCGUGCCAGCUCCGUGGGUGUCCUCCCAGGGAGCUUCUCUUCUCAACAGGCCUUGCGAGGCUGGGGUGAGAGGUGAUAGAGGCAGCACUGUGCAUGAUUCCGAGAGGGUGUGGUGGCACUGCCAGCCGACUGCUGACAGCUUGGGAGCUGCUGUGCCCAGGACGUGGGUUCAGCGUGGGCGAGGAAAGCCUGGCGAGCGUGGCCCUGUAAAAGCUUUCUGAGGCGGGAGGCGCUCACUUACCUCUGACUGCCUGGGCGCUGCGUGUAGCAUCUUGGCCUACAGGACAGAUUUUAGGUGACACCUGGUUAUGACAGUCAGAAAUUUGAGAAGCUUCUCACAAGUGAUGCACUUUAAAUAAUCUGCAUGCCAUUGAGACACCUGCAUGUCUGGUGUUUGUGGUUCAAGUGUCUUGCCGCCGGCCUUCGGAUGUAAACCCACUGAUAACGGACAGAAAGAGAAUGCCCACAAGUGGGUCUUCUGUGGAAGAUGCAGAAGGAGGAAGUUAGUGCUUACAUUUUAGUCUUUUUCUCCCUCAAAAAAAUAGGUUAAGUUUCAGUGCCAGCUAGAAAAUACUGCUUUCUGCCAUCGAUUGGGGGUGGUUUUUGUCAAAUAUACUGUUGAUAAAUAUUUAUUUUUGUAAACUUGAAGUGUGUGGUGGCCGUGGGGGAGGGACAUGCUGGCAGCAGGCGCCUUCUUCAGCUGUGGGUCCUAAAGGCCUUUGAUCCUUUGAAGAAGAAAGACAUGGUAUUUGUUCAGCAGACGCCGACCACUCAGACGGAGGGGCCCCUGGGAUUCCCUGUCUCAGAUGGCCUGGUCUUACGCCUGUGUAGAUUUCUUCUCCAUUGGGAAUGAAGGUGUCAGGCGGGACUGGAACGUUCUAGAUGGUAUGUUCCGUGAUAUUAACAACUCUAACCCAGGACAGACCACAAGCCACACUCAGAGGCCUCACUGUGCUGGGGGCUUCGGUGUCCAGGCGCCCAGGUGUGGCCACCAGCACCGGUUUCUGCCUUCGCGUUGCUGGGGUGCAGUGAGACUGCCACACGCGUGCACAUGUGGCUCUGUGGGUGUCUCCUAGAGAGGACGUGGCCCCUGCUGCCAGCCCUUGAGCAGCCCGUGUGGGGGCCCGAGGGACCCACACAGUGGGGGCCAGCCUCGCUGGAGGGAGAGCAACCCUUUGCCGAUGACCACGCUUGCCGCCAUCUCUUAGUUUUCUUUUUCACAAGCGCUUUAUUUUUUUAAUAGACAAAUCACAUUUUGCAAGGCCUUUAAUUAAAUAAGAUUCUUCUUUCCUUCAUUUUAUGCUUUAUUUCCUGUUUGAAGGCUUACUGUAGAAGUGGCUUACUGUAGAAGCAGCUUGCUGAGCCCCUCCGAGCGGUCCCCAGAAUUAGCUGGUUCACAACCCCCACCCUCCCCCGCCCCCGCCUGUGUCAGGUGUGGAUGAGGUCGUCACACUCAGAAGGACAGGCUUGUCUGCCAGCUCACAAGGGGAGGCUGCAGUGGGUUUGGGAGCUGGGUUUAGGCCCCUGGUGUCUGAGGGCCCAGGCCUUGCCAGCCUCUGCUGCUCCUGCUCCUGGGUUUGAAGAUGCAGGCCGAUCGCCAGCUCCGUGGCAGCGGUCACUAAGGACAGCCUGACUGUGCCAUCUUGGAGCCUCAGGCGGGGCUCCGGAGAUAGAAGACAGGUCGCCGGAGGCUCCCCCUCCUCUCCUCUCCCCUCUGCAGAUGCUCCCUGGGCGCUACCCUGCAGGGUGCCAGGCAGGAGUGGUCUCAGAACGUGCGCUUCUGAUUAUUUUACUGGGGUCCAUUGUCCAGAUUUUUCUUUGAUUGUAAAAUAUAUUUUUACUUUUUAGUCUUCUAAUUUAAUAAAUGAUCCAUAUAAAAAUAGAGAAAUAAAGUCCUUUAAGGGAAGGUUUA